GCGGGUGGGUCUAGACGCGCGGCAGGCGCGCCCGCUACCCGCUCUCCUCCGCGCGCCACCCGAGCCCCGCCGCCUCCCCAGCUGCCGGGAGCGGGGCCCAGGCCCCGCCGUCGCGCCAGCCCCGCGGCCCCAGCGGGCCGGGCACUCGCAGCCGCGCUCGGGCCGGCGGACGCUCGCGCCGGCUCACCAUGCACUGCCACGCCGAGCUGAGGCUGAGCUCGCCCGGCCAGCUCAAAGCAGCCAGGCGGCGCUACAAGACUUUCAUGAUCGACGAGAUCCUCUCCAAGGAGACCUGCGAUUACUUUGAGAAACUUUCCCUCUACUCCGUGUGCCCGUCGCUGGUCGUGCGACCCAAGCCCCUGCAUUCCUGUACGGGCUCCCCUUCCCUGCGGGCAUAUCCGCUCCUCUCGGUGAUCACCCGCCAGCCCACUGUCAUCUCCCACCUGGUCCCUGCCACCCCGGGAAUCGCCCAGGCACUGUCCUGCCACCAGGUCACCGAGGCGGUCUCUGCUGAGGCCCCAGGGGGCGAGGCCCUAGCCAGCAGCGAGUCAGAGACGGAACAGCCCACGCCCCGACAGAAGAAGCCCCGCCGGAGUCGCACCAUCUUCACCGAGCUGCAGCUCAUGGGCCUGGAGAAGAAAUUCCAGAAGCAGAAGUAUUUGUCAACCCCAGACAGGUUGGACUUGGCUCAGUCUCUGGGACUCACUCAGCUGCAGGUGAAGACCUGGUAUCAGAAUCGCAGGAUGAAAUGGAAGAAAAUGGUUCUUAAAGGUGGACAGGAAGCACCCACAAAACCCAAAGGUCGCCCCAAGAAGAACUCCAUCCCCACAUCAGAAGAGAUUGAAGCUGAAGAGAAGAUGAACAGCCAGGCCCAGGGUCAGGAGCAGCUGGAGCCCUCUCAGGGGCAGGAGGAGCUCUGUGAAGCACAGGAACCGAAAGCACGUGAUGUCCCCUUAGAGAUGGCAGAGCCACCAGACCCGCCCCAGGAGUUGCCAAUACCCUCUUCGGAACCCCCACCAUUAAGCUAAAGUAAAACCCUUUUGAGGGAAGAGGGAGACUGGGGAGAAGGGAAAAGAGAGAAGGCAGGGAGAGUAGGGAGAGAAAACCUUCCAGCAGCCCAGUAAACUGCGGGCGAAGAGAUCUACCCGUCUCCCUCCCUCCCACAGUUACCAUUGGCCUUGUCAUCGCAAGCAUUUGACAAAGACUUGCUUGUCUUGGGCCUGUCACCUCCUGAAAGGCUGCUUUAGCUGUGGAUGCCCUUGAUUAAGGGAGAGAGCGCCUAGGAGCUGCCUGCCCCAGCUGGGGUGACGGCUGUAGGGCUGGGUCUAUGUUGCAAGCCCUAUAUCCUAGCAUGCAGUGGAAAGUGCUUAGCUCUCUCCCUCCUGACCUCUGGGCAGCCAGUCAUCAAAGCAGAGAGACGUGGCGGCAUGUGGGCAGCAUGCCCAGGUUCCUUGCUGACUCAGCACUUAUUUCUGUAGUUUUAAAAAAGAAUUUAAUGUUUUUGGUUGUAUUUUUUUGGGGGGGUGAGGGUGGGCAAAAACAUGGGGGUAGUUCUGAGUUGUUAGAAAUGUUUCUGAAUCAAGUUUGUUUGAAGACACGUGUGCCUUUGUACCCAUUAUAAGAUGGUCAUAAGACCCAAGAACUGAUAAGCUUUGGUUUUUUUUUUGUUUUGUUUUGUUUUUUGCUUCAUUUACCCAUUCAUGCCUAGGGUUCCAUUAUUGGAACCCUAAGCUUGUGGGAGUUAUUUCUAUCCUACUGCUCAAGGUCAUCACCAAGAUCUGAUUUUUCAUAAAAAACAUUUGUGACCUUCGGCAUAAAUGGGUUAAGGUGCCAUCCCUGAAACUGCAAUGCAGAUAUGUUCAGAUAACUUUUAUUUUUUAAUUAAAAAUAAAUCUUUCAAAAGGA